UCCAGCCUGGGUGACAGAAUGAGAACUCUGUCUCUAGGGGAAAAAAAAAAUCGGAAACUCGGGCUGAGAGAGGGCAGGUCACCUGCCAGAGGCCCGCAGGUGGGGCUGGCCCUGCUGCACCUGGAGGGUGGUUCUCUCCGAGCCAGCCUUUCAGGUAGGCACUGUGACUGUCCCCACAGCACAGGUGAGAAAGCUGCAUCACAGAGAACUUGUUAAGUGACUUGCCCAAGGCCACACAGCGGCCAGGGGUGGAGGUGGAAAUCUGAGUCGGGCGGUCUGGCUUCAAUGUCAACACGCAUCACCGCUGCACCUGGCUGUCCUAGAGAUGACUCUCGAAGACAUUGUGCAGAGAGAGCACCUCUGAGACGUCCCUGUACCAGGUCCUGCUGGGGGCAAGGCAGCUAGUGCAGCCGGGACCACACGCUAUGUAUGCCCGGGUGAGGCAGGUGGAGAGCAACCCCCUGUACCAGGGCACGGCCUCCAGCGCUGACGUGGCCCUGGUGGAGCUGGAGGCACCAGUGCCCUUCACCAAUUACAUCCUCCCCGUGUGCCUGCCUGACCCCUCGGUGAUCUUUGAGACGGGCAUGAACUGCUGGGUCACUGGCUGGGGCAGCCCCAGUGAGGAAGACCUCCUGCCCGAACCGCGGAUCCUGCAGAAACUCGCUGUGCCCAUCAUCGACACACCCAAGUGCAACCUGCUCUACAGCAAAGACACCGAGUUUGGCUACCAACCCAAAACCAUCAAGAAUGACAUGCUGUGCGCCGGCUUCGAGGAGGGCAAGAAGGAUGCCUGCAAGGGCGACUCGGGCGGCCCCCUGGUGUGCCUCGUGGGUCAGUCGUGGCUGCAGGCGGGGGUGAUCAGCUGGGGUGAGGGCUGUGCCCGCCAGAACCGCCCAGGUGUCUACAUCCGUGUCACCGCCCACCACAACUGGAUCCAUCGGAUCAUCCCCAAACUGCAGUUCCAGCCAGCGAGGUUGGGCGGCCAGAAGUGAGACCCCCGGGGCCAGGAGCCCCUUGAGCAGAGCUCUGCACCCAGCCUGCCCGCCCACACCAUCCUGCUGGUCCUCCCAGCGCUGCUGUUGCACCUGUGAGCCCCACCAGACUCAUUUGUAAAUAGCGCUCCUUCCUCCCCUCUCAAAUACCCUUAUUUUAUUUAUGUUUCUCCCAAUAAAAACCCAGCCUGUGUGCCA